AGUUCACCUGCCCCACAGCCGCACCCUGCCUGUGCCUGCACCCUGGGGAGCCCAGAGCCGGCAGGGGCCGAGGCGGUGGGACCUCGGGGGAGCUCAAGCCUCGACUGUCCCCUCGCUGGAGGCCAGAGGCCAAGAUGAUGUCCAUGCUGGGCGGCUUGCAGAGAUACUUCCGGGUCAUCCUCCUCCUCCUCCUGGCCCUGACUCUGCUCCUGCUGGCCGGAUUCCUGCACUCGGACUUAGAGCUGGACACACCCCUGUUUGGGGGCCAGGCUGAGGGGCCGCCGGUCACCAACAUCAUGUUCCUGAAGACGCACAAGACGGCCAGCAGCACGGUGCUCAACAUCCUCUACCGCUUCGCCGAGACCCACAACCUGUCCGUGGCGCUGCCCGCCGGCUCACGCGUCCACCUGGGCUACCCCUGGCUCUUCCUGGCGCGCUACGUGGAAGGCGUGGGGUCGCAGCAGCGCUUCAACAUCAUGUGCAACCACCUGAGGUUCAACCUGCCUCAGGUGCAGAAAGUCAUGCCCAACGACACCUUCUACUUCUCCAUCCUGAGGAACCCCGUGUUCCAGCUGGAGUCCUCCUUCAUCUACUACAAAACCUACGCCCCCGCCUUCCGGGGCGCCCCGAGCCUGGACGCGUUCCUGGCCUCGCCGCGGACGUUCUACAACGACAGCCGCCACCUCAGGAACGUCUACGCCAAGAACAACAUGUGGUUCGACUUCGGCUUCGACCCCAACGCGCAGUGCGAGGAGGGCUACGUGCGCGCGCGCAUCGCCGAGGUGGAGCGGCGCUUCCGGCUGGUGCUCAUCGCCGAGCACCUGGACGAGUCCCUGGUGCUGCUGCGGCGCCGGCUGCGCUGGGCGCUGGACGACGUGGUGGCCUUCAGGCUCAACUCCCGCAGCGCGCGCUCCGUGGCCCGCCUGUCGCCCGAGACCCGGGAGCGCGCGCGGAGCUGGUGCGCGCUGGACUGGCGCCUGUACGAGCAUUUCAACCGCACCCUCUGGGCGCAGCUGCGCGCCGAGCUGGGGCCGCGGCGGCUGCGCGGGGAGGUGGAGCGGCUGCGCGCCCGGAGGCGCGAACUCGCGAGCCUGUGCCUGCAGGACGGCGGCGCGCUCAAGAACCACACGCAGAUCAGAGACCCGCGCCUGCGCCCCUACCAGUCCGGCAAGGCCGACAUCCUGGGUUACAACCUCCGGCCGGGCCUGGACAACCAGACGCUGGGCGUGUGCCAGAGGCUUGUGAUGCCUGAGCUCCAGUACAUGGCCCGCCUGUACGCCCUGCAGUUCCCGGAGAAGCCCCUCAAGAACAUCCCGUUCCUGGGGGCGUAGAGGGGCCGGGCCGGGGACGAGGCCUCCUGCGGACACCAGCUCCUCUCUCCGCCGUCACCGGGGAGGCCGGGGAUCCUUGCAGGGCUUCUGGGGCGUUGGGAAACCCAGGCCCGCCGGCCAC